GUCUGCUUUCUCGGCUUGAGCUUCAGGAAAGAAAACCGUCCUGGGGUACAGAAAAACUCAGAACUUUUUGGUUUUCAAACUUAGAAGGCUUUUUAAGUCUCUUGGGCUAUUUGAAAGUGUUGGUACAUACAAUGACGUUUAGUCACCAGUAUUAAGGGAAAUAAAAGCCUUUUUCAAAACGAAGCUUCCAUAGUGUCCAUGCAUUUGGGAAAUACUAUAUUUGAUUUUUUGCAUGUAUGAUUAUACCAUGAGAGACAGGAUUAAUAUAGAAGAUGGCAAGGCAAAUUUCUAAUUAGAGGGAAUAUUAAUUUUCUACAAAAUAAAGUUUGUUCAUCAAUACAAACCUGCUUUCAAAUCAAAUCAGAAAGACAUCCUUCGGAAUGUGUUCAGAACCCAAACAUCAUGUCAAUGGCAACAGAACAGUCGAACCUUUCCCAGAGGGAACACAGAUGGCUGUAUUUGGAAUGGGAUGUUUCUGGGGAGCUGAAAGGAAAUUCUGGGUCUUGAAAGGAGUGUAUUCAACUCAAGUUGGUUUUGCAGGAGGCUAUACUUCAAAUCCUACUUAUAAAGAAGUCUGCUCAGAAAAAACUGGCCAUGCAGAAGUCGUCCGAGUGGUGUACCAGCCAGAACACAUGAGUUUUGAGGAACUGCUCAAGGUCUUCUGGGAGAAUCACGACCCGACCCAAGGUAUGCGCCAGGGGAACGACCAUGGCACUCAGUACCGCUCGGCCAUCUACCCGACCUCUGCCAAGCAAAUGGAGGCAGCCCUGAGCUCCAAAGAGAACUACCAAAAGGUACCCAAGCAUGUUCACUGGAAGAAGAGAACACAGACUGGGCUGCAGACGGAGGGAAGAUGAGUAUAGGGACUCUCCUUGUCUGUCCCUGUACCUGCCCACUGCCACCUGUCUACGUCCUGAGAUACCCAGCAGAGGACAGGGUUCCACUUGGAAAAUUCUUUUGAAUCUCACACAAGACAGUAAUAAACAUAGAGGGAGAAAUAACAAGACAUUUUACCAUGUCUUGUGUCAUGUAGGAAACUUUACAUUUCAGAAAAUAUGAAGACAAAAAGAUGAAGGAAAGGGCUUUAAGGAUACAAAGGACCUUAUUAUGGAAGGAAAGCAGUGUUGUCAAGAGAGCUAAAAUGAACUUUUCUUUUUCCAGUGGGUUAACUUUUAAAAGUGCAUGUUAUUUAGUGCCCUGCAUUGCAGUGUAUCUUAUUAUAACCUUACCAGCCCCAGCUCCUUCACUGUUUUCAGUGUUUGCUAAUAUGGUAAUCAUGAAAUAGCACUUUAUUUUUGAAUCUUUGGUUAGCAUUAGAGUUUAAGUUUAUCAUUUGCUUUUUGUUUGUAAGCCCUGAAUGAAGGUUUACUUGCACUUAGGAAAGCCCACUGUCCAGUAUGUAGACAAGUUAGCUCACUGAAGGUCUUACUAAGCCAUUAGUUGAAUUACAAUGCAUCUGCUACAGCCUGGAUCUCUAAAUUGAUGGAAUCCACAUUGUUGGCAAGAUUCAAGGGUAGCACACACCCUGAACACACAAAUGCGAGGACACAACAGCAAGAAUGAGUAAGCGAGAGAAUCAGGUGAGUUUCUAAGGAGCUUUCUGGAGGAACAGAACUUUGUUUUACUUUUUGAUUAUGCAAUUUAUGUUUAUAGUGGAAAACAGGUAAGACAAUAAUAGUACCUUUGCUAAUCAUAUUUUAAAACAUUUUGGUAUGUAUGCUUCUAUUCCUUUCUCUAUGGGAAUAAAUACCUUAAACAAUAGAAUCAGUAUAUUCGUGAAAUAUCGGUCAGUAAAAUCAGAUUAGAAUGAUUACAAAUGCAUCGGUGAAGGUAUUAUCAGUGAAAAUAUUUGUAACCUGCAUUUUCGCUGCAUAUUCAUUUCAUGAAUAUCUUUUCAUACCAGUUAUGUAAUAUGUGUGUGUGUGUGUGUAUAUAUAUAUAUAUAUAUAUAUAUAUACCAGUUAUAUAAUAAAAUGUUAUUUUAUUGUUA